GUCCCCCGCUUGGCUUCCAGCGCCGCUUGCGCUCCGGAGCGCUGGCUCUGCUGGCGCUGAGAAAUGGACCAAUUUUGACAAGAUAUAGUGCUGCAGCGUGCCUGAUGGGAUAUAUUCAGUCAUGGCGUCCGAACUUUGUAAGACGAUCUCUGUGGCAAGGCUAGAAAAGCACAAGAAUUUGUUCUUAAAUUAUAGGAAUCUGCACCAUUUUCCAUUGGAGUUACUGAAAGAUGAGGGACUGCAGUACUUGGAGAGACUCUAUAUGAAAAGGAACUCCCUGACAUCCUUGCCAGAAAACCUUGCUCAGAAGCUUCCAAACCUUGUGGAACUAUACCUGCACUCAAAUAACAUAGUUGUGGUUCCGGAAGCCAUUGGGUCUCUUGUAAAACUCCAAUGUCUGGAUCUUAGUGACAAUGCCUUAGAAAUUGUUUGCCCAGAAAUUGGUCGUCUGAGAGCUUUACGUCAUCUUCGAUUAGCUAAUAACCAACUGCAAUUCCUACCUCCAGAGGUUGGCGAUUUGAAGGAGCUGCAGACACUAGACAUUUCUACCAAUCGUUUGCUAACUUUACCCGAGAGGCUUCACAUGUGCCUUUCUCUGCAGUACCUCACUGUGGACCGAAAUCGUCUAUGGUAUGUGCCGCGCCAUCUCUGCCAGCUGCCCAGCCUCAAUGAGCUCUCCAUGGCUGGAAACCGUCUUGCAUUUUUGCCACUUGAUUUAGGUCGAUCUCGAGAACUACAGUAUGUAUACGUGGAUAACAACAUUCACCUGAAAGGCUUGCCAUCUUAUCUGUACAAUAAAGUCAUCGGGUGCAGUGGGUGGCGAAUAAAGUGCCUGCAAUCACCAUGGUACAUAGAACGAUGCCAGCAAGCUCCAAAGCUGAAGGCACUUUUUCCCACACCAAAACCUUCAGAGACCACACUGAAAUGCGAUCUGCAUCUCUGCCACAAUUAAGGAGUAGCUUUUAAGAAAAAGUGCCUUAUACUUUGUCGUUUAGAUAUAGAUGUUAUUGACUACUAGAAAGUUCUGUUUGUGCUAAGUAGAGAGAUAUUUUUAAAUCUUUGACUUGGUGUCUGGUAGCAGUGGUAGUGAAUUUCAUGAGAACUCCAAAUCUUUUUAAAAAAACAAAACACUAGGGGAAAAUACACAAAUUAUUAGGUAAUAGUCUACUUUUUUAUUAUUAAACUUUUGUUAUAGUAAUAGAGAAAUAAAAUUAUUAACAGGAUAGUAUCAAACAACCAGUUUUCUAAUAGUAGUAUUGAGGUAAUAAGCAGUCCUACUUACAAAUGGCCUAUAAUCUAAAGGCAUUUUUAGCCUGUUGGUUUAAAUCAAAACUCGAAAUGCUUUCUUCAUAGAAACAGCUCUGGCCACUGUAUUCCUAAGCAAACUCAUUAAAGAGUCAUUUGACCUAUUUUGCACCCCCAAAAUUAUACUUACAAUAAUACUUCUAUGGCAAAAUGUGCUCAGAAUUUUAAUAGAUGAUAACUACUGAAGCUUUGACAACAAGCAUUAAGAGUCUUCUUUCUUCUGCCUCUUUUAUCUGUUGGAUAUGUGAAAAGGGACUUCCCAGUUCCAGUUCAAAGUAGUGUUGCUUAGUGCCUCAGCCUAAAGGAAAGGAGGGGGAAGGGGUAGUAGCACAAGGGCCUGGGGGAAAUCUAGUAAAAGGACAUACGUGUGUUGAAAGCCUAGAAAGUGCCCUUCUUGAUUCAGAACACGAAUUUUGGUCCAGUUGUUCCUUCAGUGAACAUUUAUUGAGCAACUACUCUGUUUGGUCACUGUAUGAGAUAAUGGCUGUACAGUGAUGAGCUAAGCGAUGCAGUACCUGCCCGCAUGGACCUUCUGAUCUAGCCAGGGAGUCAAGCAAACCCUAAAUAAUUUAACAAACUUGGUACUAGUUCUCUUUAAGGAGGUAAUAUUUAAUCUGAGACCUGAAAGAUCAACUCCCUUCGUUCUUCACUGCUAUCAUAUGUUGCAUCUGACCUAGAUGUAGGCUUGGGAUAUAAGAACAGUUUCUGCUGUGCUGUACAAGCUCUGAAGCAAUUACAGUACCCUUUUCAGAUUGAGGGUCUAAGAAUUAGAGCAACAACUGAGCAAAAUGAACACAGCUUUAGGUACUUGUGGGACAAUAUAAGAAAAGUCUGAGAUAUAUACGUAUUUAUCUCAGAUUCACAUCUCAGAGGGAGAAUAGAGAGACAAUGGGGUAUAAAACUUAUAAAUAGGUAUAAAAACAGCAAAUAACAAAUGUAGCAGUUUUAAGAAAUCUCAGAAGUCUCAUAAAAUUCUUUUGUAUUCAUGGAAAUGCAAACAAAGUUAGCUUCUUCUUAUUCUAUGUUUAUUUGUCAAAUAAUUUGUGAACAUUAGCAAAUCAGCACAGUGCUAGAAAUUGUGGGAAAAACCAAGAUAGUUUAAAUGUUUAUCUUGAUAUGCAAAAAUAACUGUAAUACAAAUAAUAAAUACCCUAAGAGAGGUAGAGUGAUGGAAAUGUAUAGCAUGGAACUGUGUUUUAUAACCUAGCUUCAAAGCCACACACUGUUGUUUCUGUUAUAUCCUGUUGAUUACACAGGUCAACCCUAUUCACAGUAGGAGGUGACUACAUGGAGAGUGACCACUAGGAGCGAGGACCAUUGGGGGCCCACUUGGAGACUGGCUGUCACAGCUUCAUGGCAUCUAUACUAUUUGCUAGCCUCAUGGAAAAGAAUGAUCUUUAUUUUUUCUGGGUUUUUCUUGUUAUUACAGGAGUAAAUGUCCUCAAUCUUCUACAUUGUAGCCAGAAAGAGAGGUUCAUCCCAUGUUAGAAUUUUAGAGAAUGGUAAUUGGCACAUAUACUUACUGAGGAGAACUUAAUGGUAAAAGUAAUCCUCUACAGGAUGUUUUUUCCAAUUGUUUAAUUAUGUAAGAAAAAAAAAAAAAAACCAAGCCACUACUUUGCUUUUUAUUGUGUAAAUAAGCAAUUAUAGCUGGAUUUGUGUCCAAAUUGGUUAAAUACUAUUCUAAUGGUUUAUUAAUAUAACCACUGAGAGUAAUAGAGUUGUUUGUAUGAGAAAUGUAUUCUGAGUUAAACCAGUAUACUAAAAGUAUCCAUUUUUAUGUAGGGGCUGCCUGCCCCCAGUAUCGGAUACCUGAAACACACUUCAGUGGAGCAGGACCAAAGUGGCCUGGCUGCAGAUGAAAGUACUCAAGUGUGAUUGAAACUGUCAUUUAAGAGACUGAGUUUGCAGUUUGACGCCCAUGAAGUUAGUUGUUGUUAAAACAAAAAUAUUAAUUACGUUUAAGUGUUAGCGGAAUAUAAGAGAACCCAGGGUCUCUACAAUAUAACUUUCACAAUAUCUAGGAAACGUUCCAAAAUUACAAGACAUGUAAAGAAUCAGGAAAAUGUGACCCAUUCUCAAGAAGAAAGAUGACCAGCAGAGACUCCAAUUUGAGAUGACCCAGAUUGUUGAAGUGACAGAGAUUUCAAAGCAACUGUUACAAUUAUUCUCAAUGAAGUAAUGAAUGAAAAGGCCAGAAAAAUAGAGACUAAAAAAAAGGAAAUUCUAGAAUUGAAAACAGUGUCUGAAGUAAAAAAUUAACUUGAUGGACUUCAUGGCAGAAUGGUUGGAACAGAGGAAAUGUCACUGAACUGGAGAUAGAUCAGUAGAAAUGAUCCAAUCUGAAGGACACAUAGAAAAGACAUUGAAAACAAAAAUGAACACAGCAUCAGGGACCUGCUAGCCAAUAUAAAAGAAUCUUAUGCAUGUAUAAUUGGCAUCCUUGAAGGAAAAUAGGGAGAGAAUGGGUAACGUCAGUAACAAACAUGUUUGAAGAAAUAAUGUUUAAAAAUUUCCCAAAUUUGAUGAGAAACAAAUUUACAUUUUCAAGAAGCAUAGCAAAUCCUAAGCAGUAUAAAUUCAAAGAAAACCAUGCGUAGGCAAAGCUGAUGGGUACAAAAGAUAAAAAGAAAAUUUUGAAAGCAACCAGAGAAAUAACAUUACAUACAAAGGAGUAAUUCAAAAAGAUUGUUAAUUUCUCAUCAGAAACUUUGAAGUCCAGAAAACAAUGCAACUACAUUUUAUAAGUGCUAAAGAAAAAAGUCAACUCAGAAUUAUAUAAAUACAUUCUCAGAACAAAACUUAGCCUUAAGUAGCUCUGCCAAGAUGACAGACUCUUUGUCCAAGCCAAGGUUUAUUCUUUCUAGGUGACAUAGUUUCUUUCCAUCUCCAUAUCCACUUCUUCCCUUUCCUUUUACUUUUAAGCUGAAGAAAAACUUUUUUGCUAAAAAGGAGAAGGAUAAAUCUGUAGUAGCUCCCACAAAAAUGCACAUGUAGAUGACACAGCAUACUUUCUGAAGGAGAAAAGAUCAUUAUUUGGGUACUAUCAAAAUUCAUACAGCUCUCACUCCCCUCUCAGUCUAUUAUAUAUUAAUGUCUGUCUCUCCUCACUAUAAUAGGCCCAGCUCUGAUCUUAAGUAUGUUCCUCACAAAUGUAUAUGCUCAUAUGUACCAAAUACACAAUUUUUAUGGAGGCACAAUUUGUAGUAGCUCCACACUACAAACAGCCCAAAUGUCCAUCAUUACUGCACAGCAAUGAAAAUUAAUAAACUACAGUACACAAAGCAACAUGGAUGAAUUCCAGAAGUAUAAUGUUGACAAAAGAAACCAGGCACAGCAACCUUCAUGCUGUUCAAAAAGGCCAAACCAGACUAUAGUGUUAGAAUUUGGAAUAGUGCUUCCCUUUGGGGUAUGGGUUUUGCUUAGCAGUGGGACCCAAGGUGGUCUUCUGAGGUUCUUGUUCUUGACCUUGGUGGUGAUUAGUGUGUUCAUCUUGUGAAAAUCACAGCAAUUGUGACUUGUGUACUUUUCUAUAUGAUUAUAUUUUUAAAUAAUGUUUUAAAUAUUUUAAAGUUUACCUUAAAAUAUCGAUAAUUUAUUCAACAUUAUAUUAAAGAAAAACACAAUUAUAUUGGUAUGUUAAGAGAAACUUUUGAUGAUUUUGUAUGAUUUCUGAUUUUGAUGAAUUCUGUAGCCACAUAUAAUAAUAAUUUUUAUAUUAAAUGAUGAUGUAUUCAAACUAUGGCCAUUAAAAUCAGGAAUAGGAGAGGAGUGAGGGCCCACUGUCACCACUGCCAUCUGUCUAAUGCAAUAAGAUGGAAAAAAAGGAAAUAGACAUUAUAAAUACUGGGAAAAAAAGAACCAGAAAGACCUUUAUAGGUGAUAUGCUUGAAUACCUAGAAAACUCAAGAUAUGCUACCAAAAAAAAUCUUUCAGACACCUAAAAGAAUUUAGUAAGGUGGCUAAAUAUAAGAUAGCAUACAAAGAUUAGCAGCUUUUCUUUAUGUCUUCGUAAAUUAGAAAUCAAAGUUAGGGGGAAAAUGUCAUUUAUCUUUGUACCACACAUUUAAAUAUACAGUAAUAAAUAUCACAAGAAAGGAACAGAAUCUAUGUGAAGAAAAUUGUGAAAUUUUUAUUAAAGGAUAGGAUAUAAAGCACUAGGUGGAUAGUACAGAGAUACCAUGUUUGCAAAUAAGGAAAUUUAUGAUCAAAUUACCUGUCUUAACAUAGAAAUCGAUGUUAAUUCUAAUACAAAUCUCUGGAAGGCUUUAGGGAAAUAGAGAUAAAAUAAUUGUAAAGUUCAAAUUGAAUGAUAACUGAGAAUUGCAAGAAAAAAAUUGAACAAUAAUAGUUAGGGCAGACUUGUCAAAUGAUAGAAUCUUCUAUAAAGUAUUGUAAUCAAAACAAUAUAGAACUGACACAGAAUUAAACUGAUACAUCACUGAAACAGACUAAAGACUCCAGAAAGCAAUGCCAGUGUAUUUGGGAACUUAAUAGGAUAAAAAGAACAGUUCAAUUCAGAGGUAAAUGAUAGUGUUGUUUAAUAAUGCUACCCGUAUUAUUUUUCCAUUUGGAAAAAAAAAGCUAUGUCCUAUUUUAUAUUAUAUAACCAAGUAAGACAAAUAGAUAAAACAUCUACACGUAAAGGCCAGGUGCGGUGGUUCAUACCUGUAAUCCCAGCACUUUGGGAAGCCGAGGCGGGCCAAUCACUUGAGGUCAGAAGUUCAAGACCAGCCUGACCAACAUGGUGAAACCCCGUCUCUACUACAAAUACAAACUAACCGGACGUGGUGGCGGGUGCCUGUAAUCCUAGCUACUCAGGAGGCUGAGGAGGUGAAUCACUUGAACCCGGGAGGCAGAGGUUGCAAUGAGUUGAGAUCACAGACUGUACUCCAGCCUAGGUGACAGAGCAAGGCUCUGUCUUAAAAAAAAAAAAAUCUACAUGUAAAAAUACAAUAAACAUACUGGAAGAAACUUUAGGAUAAUAUAUGCACAGUCUUCAAAUCAGGGUAACCCUCUUAAGAAAUUCAGAAAAAUGUAGAUACCAUGAAGGAAAUAAGUGGAUAGAUUUCACAUCAGAAAAGAAUGCUGACAAAGAGAACCAUAUGCAAAGUUAAAAGACAAAAACAUUUUUGUCGAUAAAUAUUUCAGUGCAUAUGACAAAGGAUUGUUAUUGCCAAUAUGGAAGUUCCUACAAAUUGAUAUAUUUUAAUUUAAUAGAAAAUGAGAUAAGGGAUGGACGUGGACAGUUUACAGAAGAAGAAAUGUAAAUGGCCAGCAAGGCUAACAAAAGGUGAUCAAACUCAUUAGUAACCAAGGAGGCAUUUCCAUUAAUCAGCCUAGCAAAAACUAAAAUGACUGAUAACAUCCAGUUCUGAUGAUGGUGUGGGGAAAUGGAUGCUUUCUUACCAAUCUUUUUGGAAAGAUCUCAGGCAUUUAAAAUGUUCAUUUUUCAUGGCCAGUGGUCUCAGUUUGGGAAUUUUACUAUAAUAAAAACAUCUGUGCAUUGGAAUGUA